AUUUCUGAAGUGAGACUAGGAAGAGAAGAUGAACAAUUCCCUGGAUUAUCUGGCCUACCCUGUUAUCGUCUCUAAUCACAGGCAAAGCACAACCUUCAGAAAGAAACUGGACUUUGGCCACUACGUAUCUCACAAGAAUAGAAUACAAAUAGCGAAGCCUACUGUUGAUACCAAACCUCCAGUGGCGCACACAAAUCACAUUUUAAAAUUGAGCAAACUACAGGGUGAACAAAAGAAAAUCAACAAAAUCGAGUAUGAAAACAAGCAACUGUGUCAGAAAAUCGCAAAUGCCCAUCGCGGCCCUGCCAAGGUGGAUUGCUGGAAUGAAUAUUUUUCCAAGAGCUUAAACAGAGAAACAAGGAACCGCGAGCUAGUGAGAAUCACCAUGGAAAACCAGGGCAUUCUGAAGAGGCUUGUUGAUCGCAAACCCCACUAUGACCGCAGGGCAUCUGAGAUAGACUGGCAGAAUUCAAGGCGCUAUAUCAGAAAUACCACGAGAUAUCUUCUCUCCCAAAAUGAAUAGGUUACUCACCAUGGAAAAGAUACAAGAGAAGGCCCUAGGAUUUCUUGGCUGCUCAGGAUCUCAAGACACUCCCGACUGGCUGAAUGCUCCAUCUUCAGAUGCUUCAAUAAAGCUUGGAACAUAAAAUGCGUAAGUUACAUUUAGGGGACCCAAAGGCUUUAUGUUCUCAUUCCAAAAUGGGGCAGGCAGAAGGAAAGAUGCAAUGAGCAUUUUUAUUUGGGGCUAUGAAAAGAAGUUUUAACGAGAGAGAGAGAGAGAAAUCUGAGAGAACUCUUUAAAACAUACACCAUCAUCACCAUCCCGUGGAAGAAGAAAAGCUGGGGUGAGAUCAUCCAGCCACAAGUACAGCACUGUCAAAAUGGAAAACGAAAUCACAUGACAACAUCAAGGUUCAGAAAACACAAGGAACAAAUGCCAUUAGUUCCUCUGUGAAUACACACGAUCGGAAAAGAAUGCCUCAUUGAAGUUUCCAUGGACUCUGUUCAUUUAUAGGGAGCAGCAGCAGUGAAAAUGUCUCAAAACAUACGGUGAGACAAUGUUGCAGGCCUGCUAUGAUUGGUCAUGCUAGUUUUCAGCCCAACUAUAUUAGUCAGCAUUUGCCAAAGAGACAGACUCAAUAGGAGAGAGAGAGAGAGAGAGAGAGUGAGAGAGAUAGAUAGAGAGUGAGAGAGAGAGAGAAAGAGAGAGAGAGAGGAGAGGAUUUAUUUGGGGAAUUGGCUCACAAGAUCAUGGAAGCUAAAGAAGUCCCACCACAGGCCAUCUGCAAGCUGGAGACCCUGGUGGAGCAGGGCAGACAACCCCCAAAGUGGGGCUUAGCCUGCGAGUGUUCUUGGCUUCACCCAGGAAAGAAUUUAAGGGUGAGCCAGUGGUAGGGUAGAAGAAGACAGUUUUAUUGAAGCAGCAGUGUUACAGCUCCAUGACUGCUCCUGCAGUACAGGGCUACCCCAAAGGCAGAGAGUUUUGCAGUCAUAGUUAUACGUACUUUUAAUUACAUGUAGAUUAAGGGGCGGUUUGUGCAGAAAUUCUAGGGAAGGAGUAGUAAUUUUUUUUUUUUUUUUUGAGAUGAAAUCUCACUCUGUCGCCCAGGCUGGAGUGCAGAUGGCGCGAUCUCAGCUCACUGCAACCUCCGCCUCCUGGGUUCAAGCGAUUCUCCUGCCUCAGCCUCCCAAGUAGCUGAGACUACAGGCACUCGCCACCACGCCCAGCUAAUUUUUGUAUUUUUAGUAGAGACGAGGUUUCACCAUCUUGGCCAGGCUGGUCUUGAACUCCUGACCUCGUGAUCCGCCCGCCUCGGCCUCUCAAAGUGCUGGGAUUACAGGCGUGAGCCACCAUGUCCGGCCUAUAGGAAAGGGUAGUAAUUUUUGGGUCCUUGGGUCAUUGCCCUGGAAAGGGGUGGUAACUCCUAGGUGUUGCUACGGUAAUGGUAAACUGACAUGGCACACUAGUGGGAGUGUCUUAUGGAAAGCUGCUUCCACCCCUUUCCUGUUUUAGCUAGUCCUCAAUUGGAUCCUGUGUCCAAGCCCCGCCUCUGGAGUCAAGGCCUGCCUCCCACCUCACUGGGAUGCUGGUAGCAUGGCUUGGUCCAAGCCCAAAAACCUCAGAACCAAGAAGAAGGUGGUGUAACUCUCAGUUCGAGGCCAAAGGCUGAGAACCCACUAGGGGGGACAAGGGUGCUGGUGUGAGUCUUGGAGUACAAAGGCCAAGGAGCCUAGAGUUGUUGUCCCAGGACAGGAGAGGAAGAGUGUAUUCCAGUUCCAGCAGAUAGAUUGACAUAUUCGCCUCUUGUCUGUUUUUGUUCUUUCUGAAUCCACAGCAAGUUGGAUGAUGCCUCUCCACAUUGAGAGUGGAUCUUCCCACAUAGUUCACUCAGACUUACAUGCUAAUCUCCCCUGGAAACACUCACAGACACACCCAAAAAUAAUGCUUUACCAGGUUUCUAUUCAGUCAAGUUGGCACCUUAAAUUAACCAUCGCACUGACUUUUUAAACUUUCUAUUUUGAAAUAAUGAAAAUUCACAGGUAGUUGCACAUAAAGGAACAGGGAGGCCUCCUGCACCCUUUACCCAGUCUCCACCAAUGUUAGCAUCUUGCGUAACUGGAGUACAAUAUCAAAACCAGGAAACUGACAUUGGCAUGAUGCAUGGAACCUAUGCAGGUUUCAUCAGUUAUACAUGCACUCAUUUUUGUACAUAUAUGUAUAGCUCUAUGCGGUUUUUGCCACAUGUAUAGCUUUGUGUAACCACAUUCGAGAUACUUAAAACCACUAUUAUCAAAAGACACUCUUAUUGCCACCCUUUUAGCCACAGUCACCUCAGACCCUCAAGCCUAACUCUUGGCAAUCACAAUCUGUUUUCCACCUCUCUGUUAGUUCAUGGUAUUACGUAAAUGGCGUCAUGCAAUGUAUGUUCAUCCUUUUGAGAUUGGCUUUUUUCACUCAGGAUAAUUUCCUUGAUGUUCAUCCAAGUUGUGUGUGCCUUUUUAUUGCUGAGUAGUAUUCCAUGGUAUGGACAUGCUACAAUAUAUUUAACCAUACAUCCAUCAAAGGACAUUGGGGUAGUUUCUAGUUUUUCAAACAUUAUUAUUAUUAUUAUUAUUAUUAUUUUGAGAUGGAGUCUCAUUCUGUUGCCCAGGCUGGAGUGCAGUGGCACGAUCUUGGCUCACUGCAACCUCCACCUCUGGGGUUCAAGCGAUUCUCCUGCCUCAGCCUCCUGAGUAGCUGGGAUUACAAGCAUGCAUCACCAGGCCCGGCUAAUUUUUAUAUUUUUAGUAGAGACAGGGUUUCACCAUGUUGACCCGGCUGGUCUCAAAUUCCUGACCUCAGGUGAUCCACCUGCCUCGGCCUCCCAAAGUGCUGGGAUUACAGACAUGAGCCACCACACCUGGCCUGAUUUUUUAAAUAGCAAAUUUUGAAAGUUAUUUACAUAUUAUAGGAAUAAGUCCUUUGCCUGCUAUGCGCCUUGCAUGUAUUUUUCUCCCAGUCUAUAAUUUGUCUUUUCAUCCUCAGGGUCUUUGACAGAGUAAAAUAUUUUUAUUUGGAUGACAUCCAAUAUAUCAAUGAUGAAACUGUUCUAUAUCUUGACUCUAUCAAUGUCAAUAUCCUUGUUGUGAUACUGUACCAUAUAGUUUUGCACUAUGCUACCACUGGGGGAAUCUGGUAAGGAGUUUACAGGAUCUCUCUGUAUUAUUUCCUACAUGCAUGUGAAUAUACAAUUAUCUCAAAAUAAAAAGCUUAAAAAAAA